AGUGCCCGCCCCUCUCGGCCGCCCGACGCUCUCUGCUCGCGCUUGGGCUCGCGAUGGGGAAGAAGUCCCGGGCGGUACCCGGCCGUAGGCCCAUCCUGCAACUCUCUCCGCCGGGUCCUCGGGGCAGCACGCCGGGCCGGGACCCGGAGCCGGAACCCGACACUGAGCCGGACUCAACCGCGGCGGUCCCCAGCCAGCCCGCCCCGUCGGCGGCGACGACCACCACCACCGCGGUGACUGCCGCCGCGGCCUCGGACGACUCGCCUUCAGAAGGCAAGGAUGAACAGGAAGCGGUGCAGGAGGUUCCUAGAGUUGUUCAGAAUCCUCCAAAACCAGUCAUGACCACUAGACCCACAGCUGUUAAAGCAACAGGCGGUCUAUGCUUGCUUGGUGCUUAUGCUGACAGUGAUGACGAUGACAAUGAUGUUUCCGAAAAACUAGCACAAUCCAAAGAGACAAAUGGAAACCAGUCAACUGAUAUUGAUAGUACAUUGGCCAACUUCCUAGCGGAGAUCGAUGCCAUAACAGCUCCUCAGCCUGCAGCUCCUGUAGGAGCUUCUGCUCCACCUCCAACUCCACCUCGACCAGAGCCAAAGGAAGCAGCAACAUCUACCCUUUCUUCUUCUACUUCAAAUGGAACAGACUCCACCCAAACAUCUGGUUGGCAAUAUGAUACUCAGUGUUCACUGGCAGGAGUCGGAAUUGAGAUGGGCGAUUGGCAGGAAGUCUGGGAUGAGAACACGGGAUGUUAUUAUUAUUGGAAUACACAAACAAAUGAAGUGACUUGGGAGUUACCCCAAUAUCUUGCCACACAGGUACAGGGAUUACAGCAUUACCAGCCCAGUUCUGUGCCAGGUGCUGAAACUAGUUUUGUGGUAAAUACAGACAUAUAUUCUAAGGAGAAAACGAUUUCUGUUUCCAGUAGUAAAAGUGGACCAGUCAUAGCCAAGCGAGAAGUUAAAAAGGAAGUAAAUGAAGGAAUUCAGGCUCUCUCAAAUAGUGAGGAGGAGAAGAAAGGGGUGGCAGCAUCGCUGCUUGCUCCUUUAUUGCCUGAGGGAAUAAAAGAAGAAGAAGAGAGAUGGAGAAGAAAAGUAAUUUGUAAAGAGGAGCCAGUUUCAGAAGUAAAAGAAACAAGUACAACAGUAGAAGAAGCAACAACAAUAGUAAAGCCACAGGAAAUUAUGUUGGACAAUAUAGAAGACCCUUCUCAGGAGGAUCUUUGCAGUGUUGUCCAAUCUGGAGAAAGUGAGGAGGAAGAGGAACAAGAUACCCUUGAACUGGAGCUAGUUUUGGAAAGGAAAAAAGCAGAGUUGCGAGCCUUGGAGGAAGGAGAUGGUAGUGUGUCAGGGUCUAGUCCACGUUCUGAUAUCAGCCAGCCAGCAUCUCAAGAUGGAAUGCGUAGGCUUAUGUCUAAAAGAGGAAAAUGGAAGAUGUUUGUUCGAGCUACCAGUCCAGAAUCUACCAGUAGGAGUUCUAGUAAAACUGGACGAGAUACUCCAGAAAAUGGAGAAACUGCAAUUGGUGCUGAAAAUUCAGAAAAAAUAGAUGAGAAUUCAGAUAAAGAGAUGGAAGUAGAAGAAUCUCCAGAGAAAAUAAAAGUACAGACAACACCAAAAGUAGAAGAAGAACAGGAUUUGAAAUUUCAGAUUGGAGAACUGGCAAAUACCCUGACAAGUAAAUUCGAGUUUCUAGGCAUUAAUAGACAAUCCAUCUCCAACUUUCAUGUGCUGCUCUUACAGACUGAGACUCGAAUUGCAGACUGGCGGGAAGGGGCUCUUAAUGGAAACUACCUUAAACGAAAACUUCAGGAUGCAGCAGAACAACUAAAACAGUAUGAAAUAAACGCCACUCCUAAAGGCUGGUCCUGCCACUGGGACAGGGAUCAUAGACGGUAUUUCUAUGUAAACGAACAGUCGGGCGAGUCUCAGUGGGAGUUUCCAGAUGGUGAAGAGGAAGAAGAAGAAAGCCAAGCACAAGAAAAUAGAGAUGAGACUCUUGCCAAACAGACCUUGAAAGACAAAACUGGCACUGAUUCAAAUUCAACAGAAUCCUCUGAAACUUCCACAGCAGUUAAUGAACUGAAGAGGCUUGAUCGUAGUUCUGGAUAGGUGGCUCCACUCCUGACCACUGUCAACAUCCCUUAUAUGUUCCAAAGUUGAAAAUUCCACUGUUACCAAUUCUGAAUGUUCUGUGAACACUUUAGAUGAGUAUUAAGCUGUUUUCUCCCUUUAUGACACACAUAGUUGAUACUGUCUGGUAAAAGGAGGCUCUUGAGCCAUUCCUAUUUAAUUAAAACAGAACUAGUUGUAGUGUAGGAAAAAGCCACUGAUAAAACAGGUUAUAUUCUUAAGCCUCUCUUUAUUGAGAACCCCUAGAAUUGCAGGAUAAACUUGAUCGAAGUAAAAUCCAAAUCUUAAACUAAGUUCUGUGAGAUUUAAGAGCAAUAAUCAACAGUUCUAAGCCUAAUAAAGAGAGCUCUUAAUCAGCUCAGUGGUGGUUAAAACCAGCUAUCUUUUAAAGAAGAGAAAAAACAAAACACAGCAAUGCCCUGUCUCUUCAGAAAAUUGUUUUAAAAAGUUAGCCAGGCAUAGUUAGUGGCCCACGCCUGUAGUCCGAGCUGUUUGGGAGGUUGAGGUGGGAAGAUUGGUUGAGCCCAAGAUUUUGAGGCUGCAGUAAGCCAUAAUUGUACCACUGCACUCCAGCCUGAGCGACAGAGAACAAGACCCUGUCUCAAAAAUAAAGUGGGGGAAGGGGUGCAAAAUUACACUGUGAGAAGCCAAGAAGUUUCAAAGUUCUAUUUAUUUUUCUAAGUCAUUUUUAAUCAUUAUUUGUUGUUUCAGUGUUUGAAUUUAACAUUAUGUUUUUAAAGAUGGAGUGGAUUCUAAAGAUGAGUUGGGUUCAAGAUAUCCAACAUAUCUUUUAUAUUGGGCUUAUGUCACUUAGGUGAAGUUGAGCUCCUUUUUCUUUUUAAUCUCCAUGGAACAAUUUGUAUAAUUUCUUGAUUUAAAUUGCUAAACUGAGCUCUUCAUUCAAAAUACUAAACAAUAAUUUCUCUUUGGGGGGAAAAUUAAGGAAGGCUUUCUAUACAUAGAAAUAAAGAUGCCUAGGCCGGGUGCAGUGGCUCAUGCCUGUAAUCCCAAUACUUUGGGGGGCUGAGGCGGGUGGAUCACCUGAGGUCAAGAGUUCAAGACCAGCCUGGGCAACAUGGUGAAACCCUGCCUCUACUAAAAGUACAAAAAUUAGCUGGGCGUGGUGGCAGCUGCCUGUAAUCCCAGCUACUCGGAGGCUGAGGCACGAGAAUCACUUGAACCUGGGAGGCGAAGGUUGCAGUGAACCAAGAUCAUGCCAUUGCACUCCAGCCUGGGCGACAGAGCAAAACUCUUUAUCUAAAAAAAAAAAAAAAAAAAAAGACGCCUACAGAAGCAAGGUUCUUAGGUGCAGUGACUCAUGCCUGUAAUUCCAGCACUUUGGGAGUUUGAGGCAAGAGGAUCACUUGAGCUCAGGAAUUCAAAACCAGCCUGGGCAAUAUGGCAAGACCCCAUCUUUGCAGAAUAUUAGCCUAGCUUGGUAGCACGAGUAUGUGGUCCUAGCUACUUGGAAGGCUGAGGUGGGAAGGAUCACUUGAGCCUGGUAGGUUGAAGCUGCAGUGAGCUAUAUUCACACCAUUGCACUCUAGCUUGAACAACAAAGUGAGAUCCUGUCUCAAAAAGAAAAAGGAAAAAUUACAGCUCACGGCUGUAAUCCCAGCACUUUGGGAGGCCAAGGCGCGCAGAUCACUUGAGGUCAGGAGUUUGAGACCAGCCAACAUGGUAUCACCCUGUCUCUACUAAAAAUACAAAAAUUAGCCAGGUGUCGUGGCGGGUGCCUGUAAUCCCAGCUACUCGGGAGGCUGAGGCAGGAGAAUCGCUUGAACCCAGGAGGCAGAGAUUACAGUGAACCAAGAUGACACCUCUGCACUCCAGCCUGGGCAACAGGCUUAAAGACUCCGUCUUAAAAAAAAAUUAAGAAUUUGUAUUCUCAUAACAUAUUCAGUUUUAAGCUUGUAGCUUUUAAAUCUUUGAGCACGUAAUAAAAGCUGCGUAGGCCAAGUGUGGUGGCUCAUGCUUGUAAUCCCAGCACUUUGGGAGGCUGAGGCAGGAGGAUCACCUGAGGUCGGGAGUUCAAGAGCAGCUUACCCAAUAUGUAGAAACCCCGCCUCUACUAAAAAUACAAAAUUAGCCAGGCGUGGUCGCAUGCCUGUAAUCCUAGCUACUCGGGAGGCUGAGGCAGGAGAAUCAUUGAACCCAGGAGGCGGAGGUUGUGGUGGGCCAAUAUCACACCAUUGCACUCCAACCUGGGCAACAAGAGCAAGAGUCCAUCUAAAAAAAGAGCUGUAUAUACCACUUUAAUCUGUCCUUGGGCUUCAGACUUAAAUAUUCUCUUAAACAGCAAAAAUACUAACUAAGUUAAAUUUAAAAGCAAGGAGAAGCAUCAUUGUAAUACGACAUCCAUGUGUAUUCAAACUAGAAUUUUCUGAUGGUCUUCGUAAGAUAAAGGAGAUAAUUGUCAUUUCUAUGACACAGCUUUUAUAAUUUGAAUAAACUUAGUUGGAGAUUGGAGUAUUUUUAUUAUUUAUUUUCAUGUGAGAUGGGUAAUGUGCUGACCUCAUAACAAAGUUUGAGGGAGACACAUUGUAUGUGAGAAUUUGAAGUGCUUAUGAAGUACAAAAGCAGAGGCCAGGUGCUCACAUCUGUAAUCCCAGCACUUUGGGAGGCCAAGGCACACAGAUCACUUGAGGUCAGGAGUUUGAGACCAGCCUGGCCAACAUGGCGAAAACCCCUCUCUUACUAAAAAUACAAAAAUUAGCUGGAUGUGGUGGUGUGGGCCUGUAAUCCCAGCUACUCGCGAGGCUGAGGCAGGAGAAUCGCUUGAACCUGGCAGGCAGAGGUUGCGGUGAGCCAAGAUUGCGUCACUGCACUCCGGCGUGGACAAGAGAGUGAGACUCCGUCACAAAAAAAAAAAAAAAAGAAGAAAAGUAUUGGAUUCACAUAUUCUAAAAAUGCUCGUCAUUUGUGGCUAAUUUUAUCAAGUCUAGUUUAAUCUCAUAUUUACAGAGUUUAGUUAAUUCUAAUUAGCUUUGUUGGAGGUCAUAAACCACAUUAUUAACCUUGAACCGACUCUGUGUUUACUUGAGUUCCUCUGCAUAAUAGCAUGUCACCACCAUCAUAAACAUGUUGGUAUUGCAUUAUGCUUCUAGAGGAGACAUCCACCAAUAUUUGAAAAUCUGGCUGGUCCGAGUGCAGUGGUGUUUACAACUAAUUAAUCACAACCAGUUACAGACUUUGUUUCUUCUCCAGUCCUGCUGCUUCACUUGACUAGCCUUUUAAAAAAAAGAAAGAAAAUAGAGAAAAUCUUAACUUAUAUUUACUUACUGUAUGUUGUGAUUAGUUUAAUAGAAGGGAGUUUAAUCCUUAAUAAUUAAGUUAGUCCUCAACGUUUAUUGACUUAGUUCUGAUGUAGUCCUUGUGUACUAUUGUAUAAUGUAGACUACUUGGCCAUACUUGAUUUUGUCUAAAAGUUAAUGCAUAAAUUAAUAUUAAAUAUGGCCAAAUAUAAAAGUUUAAUGAGUCAUUUGAGGUCAUUUAGCCAGAAAACUGCAUUUAUGUUCCUGGUGAAUUUUUUUCAAUGUCCUUUUCCAAAAGUGGCAGUAAGCAGCUGUCUUAAAAUAAGGAGACAGUGGGAAUGAUGUUGUUAAAGUCUUUUAUACAAUGUAUUGUCUGUCUGUUCCAUAAAAAGUAAAACUACUCUAUUCGUGACCAGCUUGGGCAACAUAGUGAGACUGUCUCUUUAAAAAAAAAAAAAAAAAAAAAAUUAAAAAUUAGCAGGUGUGGUGAUGCACACCUGUAGUCCUAGCAAUUCGGGAAGCUGAGGUAGGAAGAUCGCUUGAGCCAAGUGUUUGAGGUUAGAAUGAGCUAUGAUCGCACCACCUACACUCCAGCCUGGGCAACAGAGCAAGACCCAAAUGGCUCAUGGUUGCUUUGUUUGUUUUACCUUGUUGAGUGCCAGUGUGUAUUUUGAGCAAAGCAGUGUAAAUGGCCUUCUUGCCCUAGAGUCUUUCAUAAUUGAGCCUUAUUUAAUCUACCACUUUUGACCAUGAAAUUUAACAGGUGACUUCUUCUGGGUAUCUACUCCAGGUGAAGUGAUAUUUUUUUUGACUGAGAUGUCUAAAGCUCUUGGAUUCCUGGUAUCUCACCAGGACAUCUUAGUAAAACAGCAAGUAUCAGAUGAGGAAUCAGACUUGAGUUCUAGCUCUGGUCUGGCCACUAACAUUGAUAUGAUCUUGGGCAAGUUAGUUCCUGCCUGGGUUUCAUUACCUUUAACUGAGGAGGUUGAAAUAGAUGAUUUCUCAUGUCUCUUCUACUCCUAAAUUCUAUGAUUUUAGGGAGAAAAUCCCCUUCAACAUUCCUGGGAUAUAUAUCUAAUAGUCCCAUAUAUUGUGAAACUUCCCUAUUGACGAUAAAGAGGGCUGGGGAAGGCUACAAGUAAGUAUAUCCUAUUUUCUCUAAUCUUUAAAGGUUUUCCCAGCAGAGAAAAGACAGUAAUCAAUGAUGGCUUUUACAAAGUUUGAGGAAAGCUGAUCCUGCAACUUUUCAGCUGCAAUUUCGUAAUGUAGACUUCAGCAACAGCAAUUUCAAAACCACUGCAGUUUUAAAAAAUCUGAGUUAUAUACUUUGAAGAUUUAUCUUCCUAAAUUUCUCUUUUAUCGCAAAAGUAAAAAUUGCCAUCCCUAACUUGUGUCUCUGUGAUAUCACAAAUGAAUGUAAUGUAUGCAAGGGUGUGAAGGAAUGAUAUAGUUGACAGUAGCACCUUGCAAAUGGAUUUUUUAAAUUUAGUAACCCAAAUUAAACACAAUGGGUAGAACUUUCCCGAGUAUUUUGAAUGAAUAUUCUGGGUUGUCUUUACUCACUUUGUCUAGCUCACUAAAAAAUAAAGUAUGUGUAAUAAUUACUGCAGGUGCACAUUAUUCACUCACUCCUUCACUUUUGAAAUAGACUCCAGACUAUUACCUUUUAUUUGUGUAUGUUGAAGCUUGUGAGUGUUUGAAAUCAAAAACUUCAAACUACAGAUUCAGAUGACUGCAUUUCUCGUUGAGUUGAUGUAAUAUUCUUCUACUCAUCCAUAAAUAUGGACCCGAAGGACAAGUAUAAUACAGAUGGGGAAGGUGCUAUGAAGUUCAUAAAUUUAUCUUUCCGUGGAAGUCAUUUCUGAACUGAGUUGUUCAAUAUUUUAGCGAUAUCAGUAUAGAAUAGAUGCCUGUGGGCCAAAUUUUUUUCAAGGAAGGAGCCAUUCCCUGCUGUUUGACACCACAUUCUGUAUUGUUUUGUACACUGUGCUAGGUUCCUAUAAAUGAUUAUCUUACUGACCAGUUGAACAUUUCUAUGAAUAUAAGCCAGGGAGUUUUUUUCUUGCUUUUUCCCUGACUCUUACCUGUUUUCAUAGGUUCUCUUUGUAAAGAAUCCUUUUCUGGUCAAGUUUCUUCUUCAUCACUCAUGCCACUUACUCCAUUCUGGACCCUCCUUCA